AGCCGCGCGCCGGCCACCCGCGCGCCUGCCGCCCGUUGCCCAGGCAACCGUCGUGCCGCGUCUUCCUGAGGUAGCUCCUGUCAGCCCACUGAUCCCACCACCCGCUCCCUACUGCCCCGCGGUCUUCGCGUGAGCUCGGAGACUGAGGGACAACAAAAAUGGCGGAGGGGAGCCAGUCGGCGCCUGAGGCAGGCAAUGAUAUGGGAAAUGAUGAUGCCAUUGGAGGGAAUGUGAGCAAAUAUAUAGUGCUUCCAACUGGCUAUUGUGGACAGCCCAAGAAAGGACAUCUUAUCUUUGAUGCUUGCUUUGAAAGUGGUAACCUGGGCCGGGUGGACCAGGUCUCUGAGUUUGAGUAUGAUCUGUUCAUUAGGCCGGACACCUGUAAUCCACGCUUCCGAGUCUGGUUCAACUUUACUGUUGAAAAUGUGAAAGAAUCACAGAGGGUCAUUUUCAACAUUGUUAACUUCAGUAAAACCAAGAGUCUCUAUAGAGAUGGGAUGGCCCCUAUGGUGAAAUCUACCAGCAGACCAAAAUGGCAAAGGCUGCCACCCAAAAAUGUUUACUACUACCGCUGCCCGGACCAUAGGAAGAACUAUGUGAUGUCCUUUGCCUUUUGUUUUGACCGAGAAGAAGAUAUUUACCAGUUUGCUUACUGCUACCCAUAUACAUACACUCGCUUCCAACAUUACCUUGACAGCCUGCAAAAGAGAAACAUGGAUUACUUCUUUCGGGAGCAGCUGGGCCAGAGUGUGCAACAACGAAAGCUUGACCUCCUGACGAUAACCAGCCCUGGAGCUGCAGCAGCUAGGAAUCAACUUGCUACCUUUCUUGCGCUGCCAGUAGGAGGUACUGGCUUGUCUGAACUCCUCCCCAGACCAUCUUCAACAACAGAACUGCAGUGUGAUGUGGCCAGUCAUAGACUGGGAGCCUUCUGAAAUGCUGACCAGGAAUUUGAAAGCCUUAAUCUGCUUGAUACCUUCUUUAAAGUCUUAUUUUGUUUAUUGUGAAUAAUUUCAAAUAUGCAGAAAAGAGUAGCGAUAUAAUGAACAGCCAUUUAUUGCCCCCAUGCCAACCCCUUGGCUUUGUCAUAUCAACAUGUGUCUUAUAUGCCAGAGUCACCUAUUUUUGGACGAAAAUUAUAAAUGUAACUGAGACUAUUCUAUACUCCUUCCUAAUACAUCUUUGUCCCUUCACCCUACAGGUAAGCACUGUCAUGAAUUCAAUGUUUUUCCUUAUCUUUGUAUCAAAAAAUGUAACUGGUAUUGCUUUACAAAUUCCUGUGGUAUCACACUAUCAAUGUCAUUCUAUGACUUUUUCCCUACUCAUGAUUAUAUUGUAGAGAUUCACUUAUAUUGAAACACAUAGCUCUGCUUCAUUUAUUUUAAUUGCUGUUAGAUAUUCCAUAUAUGAUUGAAUUACAAUUUAUCCAUUGUAUUGAUCAGAAUUUAGGUUAUUUAUAGCCACUUGCAAUUGCAAAUAAUGCUGCUUAGAGCAUUUUUGUGCAUGUCUCUUUACGUAUGAGUAUGAGAAUUUCUCUAGGGAAAAUGAUUUAUUAAUUAUAUGCAUCUUCAAAUUAACUACAUAAUGACCAAUUGUUUUCCAAAGUAAUUGAACAUAUUUACUCUUCCAAUAGCAGAAUGUAAGAGUUUUCAUUCCUCUGCAGCCUUAACACUUGAAAUUGUCAGACUUAUAAAUUUUGCCAGUUGUCAUGAUGAACAUGAAAUGGUAUCUUAUUGCUGUUAUAAUAUAUGUUUCCCUAAUUACUAAUGAGAUAGGGCAUCUUUUUAUAUCUUUAUUGUCCACUUUGGUUUCUUCUGUGAAUUGAUUUUUCAUAUCCUUUAUCUGUAUUCUAUUGGGUUGUCUCUUUUUAUUGAUUUUUAGGAGUUUAUUGUUCUGAGUAUCAGUACUGUGUCACUUAUAUACAUUGCAAACGUCUUCUCCCAGACUAUGGCUUGUAUUUUUAAAUUUUUUCCAUGAUGUGUUUUGAUAUAUGCGAGGUUUUAAAAAAUUUUUUUAUGUAGUUGAAUUUAUCGAUCUCUUGUUUUAUAGGCUUUACUUUUGUGGCUUAUUUAAGAAAUCCUCCCUAUCUAAAUAUCGUAUUCUCCUGUAUUUACUUCUAAAAUUUCUCAAGUUUUGUGUCACACUUGGGUCUUUACUUGUCUCAUUUAGGACUGAUCUUUGUAUAUGAAAUAGGAAUUUAUUUUUUUGUGUGUGUAUGGAUAACCCAUUGUCUCAGCACCAUAAACCACUAGUCUAUAUUUCUACCCAUUAGUAAUUACACAUCUGUCAUCUAUCAAUUUUACUAUAUACAAAAUCUAUUUUCUUCUCGAUACUAUUGCAUUGGCCUACCACGCUUAAUUCUGCAUCGAUUCAACAUUGUCUUAUUUAUAAUAAAUUCUAAUUUUCAUAUCAUCUUAAUAAUUUAUGGGGAAAUACCCUUGGACCUUUGCCUUUCAUGCUUAUCUUUUGAAAGCAACAAUUAAAUUUUUAAAAUACAGUAUAAUAAUCCUUAUAUUGUGACAGGUGAAUUUAAUGUAUUUUCAUUUAUUAUAAUAACUAAUAUAUUUAGACAUAUUUCUACCACCAUAUUUGUGUUUUCUGUUUAUCAUUCACUUUAUUUCUUUUCUGCCUUUUAAACAUUUUUAUAUGUUACCUUUUUUAUUGCAUUCUCUGUGGAUUUGGAUGCUAUCUAUUUUAUUUCUAACCUUAACUGGUUAUAUGUGGGUAUGUACUUAGCUAUACAUUUUCUUACAACAAAGUCUACAGUUACUGCGACUUUCUAGCAUUCUUUCAGCCACAUAAAGGCCUUACAUGCUUUAACCACCUAUUGAACACUGUCACCUAGUUAUUCUUGUUUAGACUAAGUUAAACUUUUUGGAAAAAGGAAAACAAUGUAUUAUUAUUAUUAGCUCAUUGACUUUUCCUACAUAGUUUAUGAAUUUUUGCAUUCUUUUGUUUAUUGUAUAUCAAGCCUUUCCUAUAUUACCUUACCAAAGUGCAUUCUUUAAUAGCUAUUUUAGUGAGAGUCCAUGGUAACCCUCUUAAUCUGUAUAUAUUCUUGUUUUGACUUCUGUCUGGAAUGAUAACUUGGCUGGGUAUAAAUUUGAGUUUGAGGAGGAUGUUCCUUUGAACUUUAAGGAUUUUUUCUUUGUUUGGAGCAUAAUACCAUUUAUAUAAGCUUAAAAGCAUGCAAAACAGCAGUACAUUUUGGGGAUAGUGAUGUAACCAAAAUGCAGUAGUGAUGUAUAUGUGUAGUGAUGUAACCAAAAUGCAGGUUCAGUCACUUGCCAUUUGCAGAGUCCAGUUAACAAAAAUGAAGUCUGGUAUAAAGAAAGUGACUUUUAGUCUGGGCACAGUGGCUCACACCUGUAAUCCCAGCACACUGGGAGGCUGAGGCAGGCAGAUCACGAGGUCAGGAAAUAGAGACCAUCCUGGCUAACACGGUGAAGCCCUGUCUCUACUAAAAAUACAAAAAAUUAGCCGAGCGUGGUGGCGGGCGCCUGUAGUCCCAUCUACUCGGGAGGCUGAGGCAGGAGAAUGGCGUGAACCUGGGAGGCAGAGCUUGCAGUGAGCGGAGAUCACCCAGCCUGAAUGACAAAGUAAGUCCUGUCAAAAAAAUAUAAAAAAUUUUUUAAAGUGACUUUUAAUCCCAAAACUAUCUUAGGGGAAGAAGCCGGCACUUUUAAAGGAGAAUGGCACGCAGGGGAGGAAGUGAGCAGGUUGGGGAGGUCCAUGUGCUAGCUCUGGUGCCUUAUCAACCGGGCAGUUGAGCUGGUGACUGCUUGUGCCUUCAUGGGCAGCAGUAGGCUGAAAACUCCCCAGGUGGGAGAGAGUUUUAUAGUGGGACUUUGAGUUAUGAAUCAACUGUGAUCUCUCAAGGCAGUCUCCUGGUGGGAAGGAGUUCCUUGUUGGAGCUUCUAGGCACAUAGUUAGAUAAAUUUGCCCUGUAAAGAGUGUCUGGUGAAGGGGUGGUAAAAUAUUAUAUUUGCAUUUCUACAGGGCUAAGUAGGAAGUAGGAAACCAGGGAAAUGAGAAAAGAAGAGACAGAGAGAGAAAAAUAAACUAUCUCUUAGGAAAAUGGGGGCACACCAUUACAAUCAGUUCUCCACUGCCAAGUUCCAUUUCAUUUUGUUGGGAUUUGGUUGUCACCAUAUUCAUUCUGGCUACUCCCUGCUGAAAGGAGGCAUAGUCAUUGGGUGUCAGAAUGAAACUGAUCUAUUUGGAGUUGAAAAUAUUGAUGAGUACCAAGACUUAUAGAUGAUAGUUGUUGCAUUAUGGUAAAAGGUCUGGAAAGUCACUGGGAAAGCCUGUCUUGCAUUCCCAUAUAGAGGAUGCAACAGCAGUAGAAUUCACAGUGGAGAAGUAUGCCUAUUUUUUCAUUGUCUUCUGGGAUCCAUAGUUGCUGAUGAGAAGUCUGCCAUCAUAUAAUUGUUUUGGUAACCUAUUUUUUUCUUGGGCAGGUUUCAAUAUUAUUUUUUAAUCUGAAUGUUUUGCCUUUUCACUUUGUUGGGUCUAGAUGUGAAUUUAUUUUUAUUUAUCCUGCUUGAUACUCUGAGUAUACUUUUCACUUAAGAUUCUAUGUCUUUCUUUAAUUUAGGGAAAUUAUUGGCAAAUUAACUCUUCAAAUAUUGCUUUUAUCCUUUAUUCCUUUGACUCUCUUCAACAAUUUCUAUUGGACAAAUGCUAGAUGCUAUUAAGCAGCCCUCCAUGGUUCUUAAUUGAUUUUUCAUAACUUUUAUUAUUUUUGUCUUACUGCACUGAUUUUGAAUUCCUCACAAGUAACUUGCAUUUAUAAAUUCACUUUUGACCAUGUCUAGUCUAGAUUUUUUUCUGUCUCUUUCAAUAUUUCAAUGACUAUGUUUUUUCAUUUCCAAGAUUUCUAAUUUUAUUCAUACCCACCUGUUCUUGUUUUAUUUCUGCCUGUUCUGUUUCAUAAUUUCUUGUUCAGUUUUAAUGUCUUCAUUUGUUUCUUUGAACAUCCUCAAUAUGCUUAUUUUAAAAUCUUUGUUCCAUAAAAUAAGUUUCAUCUGGAGGAAAUUCAAGUUCCAAUUGUUGAUUUUGUUUAGUAUCAUUUUUAGCAUUCGAUUUCUUCAUGUGUUUUGAAAUUUUAAUUUGUAAGAUCACUUUGAGAAGGAAAUUUUCUGGUUUUCUCUUUUCUCACCCCUCAAACUCCCACUGUGUUCACAUCUCCCUGUGUGAUGGUUUUUGCAGUUGCCUCUACCCACAUCUUCAGUAUAGGACCUGGGGAAUAUUGAGUAUAUUGCAGAUUCAAUGACAAAAAGUUAACAGAACCAUUGCAUCUGGUUCCUGAGUCUAUAUUCCUCACCUCUCUAUACCUACAAUGGAUGAGAGCUAUCUCCCAAAAGUUAUGCAGCAGCCUUUUUUUCUAGGCUCCUUUCAUGACAGGAGAGCCCCACCCAAGGUCCUUGCUCUAAGCAGAAGCUUAUCUCUGAUUCCCAUCUCCUGUAGUGUACUUUUAGUCUCCCUUAUCCCAUAGGAGGCAGACGUCCAACUGCUACUGUCUUCUUCUACAUUCAGAUUUCAGCUAGCCAGUAGCCCCAGAACCACUUACCCUUUUGCAUUUCUGUACAUUUGAGCUUUGUGGUGAUGUCUCCCACAAUGGAGCCCAACAAUAUAGUUUCAUUUCUUUUUUCACAUAUUAUCCAAUAUUACUAUUUGAUGGGAAUAAAUGGGCUUAUUGAAAUAUGAACUUAUUUAGUCGUUUGGCCCAGAAGUUCAACUACAGUUUCUUCUUUACUUUUUAGAAAGUUGAUUUUCCUAUAACCUCGUCAGUAGAAGGGAGGCAAUAUGAGGAAGUACCGUAUUCUUUUCCUGUCCAGGUAAAAUCCUUACCAGCAGACUGAGGAGAGAGACUUAUUUUUUGUCCAAGUAUACACAGUUGUAGAUAUAAUUUUUAAAAUGAAAUUUGAAUGAUACCAUAUAAACUAUUGUUAUUCGAAUGUAGUGUGAACAUCUUCCAAUAUUAUUUAAUAUUCUCUAAGAGGGAAUCUUAUAUGGCUAAAAAGCAUUCUAUUCUAUUUUUAAUUCCCCUAUUGUUGUAUAUUAUUACUGUUGUUGUCUCCAAUUAUUUCAUUACAAAUAACACCACGGUGAGCAUUCUUAUAUAAAAAUUUUGGUCUAUAUCUCUAACUAUUUCUUUAGGAAAAAUUCCUAGAAUAAGAAUUACUGAGGAGAGGUAUACAUCAUUCACUAGUUGUGACACUGAAGUAACAAUUACAUCAAAUUGCAAAAGCUUAAAAAGCAAAGGCUUAUUCACUCUUGGUACAUGUCCCUUUUGGACUGCAGCCAGUUAUGCUUUGUAUCUUUUGUGUUCUAGCAGCCAGGCGGAACAGUCAUCCUCUAUUUGUAAUAUCACUGGGUGUCUUAGUUGGGGUUCACUAAGAAGCAGACCUUUACACAAAGACUUUAGUGCAAAUUGGAGGUGAUCCCAGAGACAUUGGUAGAGGAGUGAGGAAGUGAGACAGGAAAAGAAAAAAAGCCGAGAAAGAUUCAUUAUCAAGCAAGCUACCACAGAGGGCAACUGGGACUUAAUCCCACUGGAGAGCCCAUGGAACCAGUGUGGAAAAUAAGCUACAUAGUUAUACUUCUCAGGGACAAAGGAGCAGGAGAGAGGGUGGAGGUGUUGAUUCCCUGACACUUCUGAUCUGCUCAAUGUAUGCAAUGACCAGAUUCCAAUGGGUCAGAGAAAACCUUCGGGAUGGAUUUGCAGGUGUUGCCAGUUGGAAGUUAUUCAACACAUCCAGAAAUAAUAAGCUGGGAAAAUAGGUUGGAUUGUGGGGAGGCCUAGCAUUUGCCAUGUUAGUCAUUGUGACAGAGGGAAAAGGGAGGGAUGAGGAGCCACGACUCUCCCCUUAAAAACUCUUAGAAGGCGUCACUUCUGCCUAAAUAUCCUUGAUCAAAGCAAGGAUUUGAAUUUAUGGUCAUAUGACCAUAAAUUCAAAUGGGUAGAUAUGUGCAAUCUUCCCAUAGGGAAGUGCACUGCAAUGAGGAUGACAUGAAUAUUUUUCAAUGACUAAUAUACUUUAUCAUACUUUUAGAAAGAUUUUUAUAUUCCCACCAAGUUAAAAGUGCUGGUCAUACCUUUUUUUAAUAACAGCUUUAUUGAGAUAUAAUUCACAUGCCAUAAAAUCCUCAUUAAAGUGAUAAUUUAGUGGUUUUCAGCAUAUUUACACAGUUGUGCAACCAUUACCACUACCUAGUUCCAGAACACUGCCAUCACCCCAAACAUAAACUCCAUACCGACUGGCAGUCAUUCUCAAUUUCUCCUUUUCCUGACCCCUGGCAACCGCUGUUAUAACUUUCUGUCUCUAUGGAUUUGCCUAUUGUGGACAUUUUAUAUAAAUCAAAUCAUACCAUAUAUGGCCUAUUGUGACUGGCUUUUUUCACUUACCACAGUGUUUUCAAGGUUCACCCAUGUUGUAGCAUGUAUCAGCAUACUUCAUUCCUUUUUCUUGCCAAAUAGUAUUACAUUAGAUACACCACAAUUUAUUUUUUCAUUCAUCUGUUAUUGGACAUUUGGGAUGUUUCCAUUUGGGGAUUUUACGAAUAAUCUGCUAUGAACAUUUGCACAAAAGUUUUUGUGUGGACAGAUGUUUUUAAUUAUCUUGCAUAUGUACCUAGGAAUGGAAUUGCUAGUCAUAUGGUAAACUUUACAAUAAAGAUUUUGAGAAACUGCCAAA